GCACUGAGCCUAAGCAGCCGGUGAUGGCGGCAGCGGCUGUGGUGGCUGCGGCGGGUCCGGGCCCAUGAGGCGACGAAGGAGGCGGGACGGCUUUUACCCAGCCCCGGACUUCCGAGACAGGGAAGCUGAGGACAUGGCAGGAGUGUUUGACAUAGACCUGGACCAGCCAGAGGACGCGGGCUCUGAGGAUGAGCUGGAGGAGGGGGGUCAGUUAAAUGAAAGCAUGGACCAUGGGGGAGUUGGACCAUAUGAACUUGGCAUGGAACAUUGUGAGAAAUUUGAAAUCUCAGAAACUAGUGUGAACAGAGGGCCAGAAAAAAUCAGACCAGAAUGUUUUGAGCUACUUCGGGUACUUGGUAAAGGGGGCUAUGGAAAGGUUUUUCAAGUACGAAAAGUAACAGGAGCAAAUACUGGGAAAAUAUUUGCCAUGAAGGUGCUUAAAAAGGCAAUGAUAGUAAGAAAUGCUAAAGAUACAGCUCAUACAAAAGCAGAACGGAAUAUUCUGGAGGAAGUAAAGCAUCCCUUCAUCGUGGAUUUAAUUUAUGCCUUUCAGACUGGUGGAAAACUCUACCUCAUCCUUGAGUAUCUCAGUGGAGGAGAACUAUUUAUGCAGUUAGAAAGAGAGGGAAUAUUUAUGGAAGACACUGCCUGGCUUGAGUGGAACGCUCUUCACACCAGUUGUUCCUAACAGAACCAUUCUCAUUGCGGCUUUCUUUCCUUGAAUUGGCCUUUUCUAACAAAGAAGCUGCAUUUAAGAGCCUUAGGGAUGAAGUGCCCUUUUUUGGAGGAGGCUCACUGAGCCGUGUUGGAGGCUGUGUUUGUGGUCGUGCUGGCUGUGAAACUGCCUCAGUCCUCUAGGACACACCCUCUCCAUCCUGGAGUAAUCUGCAGGAUUGCAACAUUGUUAUGCAGCCAGUAUUGCAGUGCCUUGUGCUUUUCGAAUCCAGACAGGGUUGAUUCAGCCCUUUAUUCUUUUGAGCUUUUACUUGGCAGAAAUCUCCAUGGCUUUGGGGCAUUUACAUCAAAAGGGGAUCAUCUACAGAGACCUGAAGCCGGAGAAUAUCAUGCUUAAUCACCAAGGUCAUGUGAAACUAACAGACUUUGGACUAUGCAAAGAAUCUAUUCAUGAUGGAACAGUCACACACACAUUUUGUGGAACAAUAGAAUACAUGGCCCCUGAAAUCUUGAUGAGAAGUGGCCACAAUCGUGCUGUGGAUUGGUGGAGUUUGGGAGCAUUAAUGUAUGACAUGCUGACUGGAGCAGUAGCCCCCAUUCACUGGGGAGAAUAGAAAGAAAACAAUUGACAAAAUCCUCAAAUGUAAACUCAAUUUGCCUCCCUACCUCACACAAGAAGCCAGAGAUCUGCUUAAAAAGCUGCUGAAAAGAAAUGCUGCUUCUCGUCUGGGAGCUGGUCCUGGGGACGCUGGAGAAGUUCAAGCUCAUCCAUUCUUUAGACACAUUAACUGGGAAGAACUUCUGGCUCGAAAGGUGGAGCCCCCCUUUAAACCUCUGUUGCAAUCUGAAGAGGAUGUAAGUCAGUUUGAUUCCAAGUUUACACGUCAGACACCUGUCGACAGCCCAGAUGACUCAACUCUCAGUGAAAGUGCCAAUCAGGUCUUUCUGGGUUUUACAUAUGUGGCUCCAUCUGUACUUGAAAGUGUGAAAGAAAAGUUUUCCUUUGAACCAAAAAUCCGAUCACCUCGAAGAUUUAUUGGCAGCCCACGAACACCUGUCAGCCCAGUCAAAUUUUCUCCUGGGGAUUUCUGGGGAAGAGGUGCUUCGGCCAGCACAGCAAAUCCUCAGACACCUGUGGAAUACCCAAUGGAAACAAGUGGCAUAGAGCAGAUGGAUGUGACAAUGAGUGGGGAAGCAUCGGCACCACUUCCAAUACGACAGCCGAACUCUGGGCCAUACAAAAAACAAGCUUUUCCCAUGAUCUCCAAACGGCCAGAGCACCUGCGUAUGAAUCUAUGACAGAGCAAUGCUUUUAAUGAAUUUAAGGCAAAAAAGGUGGAGAGGGAGAUGUGUGAGCAUCCUGCAAGGUGAAACGACUCAAAAUGACAGUUUCAGAGAGUCAAUGUCAUUACAUAGAACACUUCAGACACAGGAAAAAUAAACGUGGAUUUUAAAAAAUCAAUCAAUGGUGCAAAAAAAAACUUAAAGCAAAAUAGUAUUGCUGAACUCUUAGGCACAUCAAUUAAUUGAUUCCUCGCGACAUCUUCUCAACCUUAUCAAGGAUUUUCAUGUUGAUGACUCGAAACUGACAGUAUUAAGGGUAGGAUGUUGCUUCUGAAUCACUGUUGAGUUCUGAUUGUGUUGAAGAAGGGUUAUCCUUUCAUUAGGCAAAGUACAAAAUUGCCUAUAAUACUUGCAACUAAGGACAAAUUAGCAUGCAAGCUUGGUCAAACUUUUUCCAGCAAAAUGGAAGCAAAGACAAAAGAAACUUACCAAUUGAUGUUUUACGUGCAAACAACCUGAAUCUUUUUUUUAUAUAAAUAUAUAUUUUUCAAAUAGAUUUUUGAUUCAGCUCAUUAUGAAAAACAUCCCAAACUUUAAAAUGCGAAAUUAUUGGUUGGUGUGAAGAAAGCCAGACAACUUCUGUUUCUUCUCUUGGUGAAAUAAUAAAAUGCAAAUGAAUCAUUGUUAACCACAGCUGUGGCUCGUUUGAGGGAUUGGGGUGGACCUGGGGUUUAUUUUCAGUAACCCAGCUGCAAUACCUGUCUGUAAUAUGAGAAAAAAAAAAUGAAUCUAUUUAAUCAUUUCUACUUGCAGUACUGCUAUGUGCUAAGCUUAACUGGAAGCCUUGGAAUGGGCAUAAGUUGUAUGUCCUACAUUUCAUCAUUGUCCCGGGCCUGCAUUGCACUGGAAAAAAAAAUCGCCACCUGUUCUUACACCAGUAUUUGGUUCAAGACACCAAAUGUCUUCAGCCCAUGGCUGAAGAACAACAGAAGAGAGUCAGGAUAAAAAAUACAUACUGUGGUCGGCAAGGUGAGGGAGAUAGGGAUAUCCAGGGGAAGAGGGUGUUGCUGUGGCCCACUCUCUGUCUAAUCUCUUUACAGCAAAUUGGUAAGAUUUUCAGUUUUACUUCUUUCUACUGUUUCUGCUGUCUACCUUCCUUAUAUUUUUUUCCUCAACAGUUUUAAAAAGAAAAAAAGGUCUAUUUUUUUUUCUCCUAUACUUGGGCUACAUUUUUUGAUUGUAAAAAUAUUUGAUGGCCUUUUGAUGAAUGUCUUCCACAGUAAAGAAAACUUAGUGGCUUAAUUUAGGAAACAUGUUAACAGGACACUAUGUUUUUGAAAUUGUAACAAAAUCUACAUAAAUGAUUUACAGGUUAAAAGAAUAAAAAUAAAGGUAACUUUACCUUUCUUAAAUAUUUCCUGCCUUAAAGAGAGCAUUUCCAUGACUUUAGCUGGUGAAAGGGUUUAAUAUCUGCAGAGCUUUAUAAAAAUAUAUUUCAGUGCAUACUGGUAUAAUAGAUGAUCAUGCAGUUGCAGUUGAGUUGUAUCACCUUUUUUGUUUGUCUUUUAUAAUGUCUUCAGUCUGAGUGUGCAAAGUCAAUUUGUAAUAUUUUGCAACCCUAGGAUUUUUUUAAAUAGAUGCUGCUUGCUAUGUUUUCAAACCUUUUUGAGCCAUAGGAUCCAAGCCAUAAAAUUCUUUAUGCAUGUUGAAUUCAGUCAGAAAAGAGCAAGGCUUUGCUUUUUGAAAUUGCAACUCAAAUGAGAUGGGAUGAAAUCCUAUGACAGUAAGCAAAAACAGAACCAUGAAAAAUGAUUGGACAUACACCUUUUCAAUUGUGGCAAUAAUUGAAAGAAUCGAUAAAAGUUCAUCUUUGGACAGAAAGCCUUUAAAAAAAAAAUCACUCCCUCUUCCCCCUCCUCCCUUAUUGCAGCAGCCUACUGAGAACUUUGACUGUUGCUGGUAAAUUAGAAGCUACAAUAAUAAUUAAGGGCAGAAAUUAUACUUAAAAAGUGCAGAUCCUUGUUCUUUGACAAUUUGUGAUGUCUGAAAAAACAGAACCCGAAAAGCUAUGGUGAUAUGUACAGGCAUUAUUUCAGACUGUAAAUGGCUUGUGAUACUCUUGAUACUUGUUUUCAAAUAUGUUUACUAACUGUAGUGUUGACUGCCUGACCAAAUUCCAGUGAAACUUAUACACCAAAAUAUUCUUCCUAGGUCCUAUUUGCUAGUAACAUGAGCACUGUGAUUGGCUGGCUAUAACCACCCCAGUUAAACCAUUUUCAUAAUUAGUAGUGCCAGCAAUAGUGGCAAACACUGCAACUUUUCUGCAUAAAAAGCAUUAAUUGCACAGCUACCAUCCACACAAAUACAUAGUUUUUCUGACUUCACAUUUAUUAAGUGAAAUUUAUUUCCCAUGCUGUGGAAAGUUUAUUGAGAACUUGUUUCAUAAAUGGAUAUCCCUACUAUGACUGUGAAAACAUGUCAAGUGUCACAUUAGUGUCACAGACAGAAAGCACACACCUAUGCAAUAUGGCUUAUCUAUAUUUAUUUGUAAAAAUCCAAGCAUAGUUUAAAAUAUGAUGUCGAUAUUACUAGUCUUGAGUUUCUAAGAGGGUUCUUUAUGUUAUACCAGGUAAGUGUAUAAAAGAGAUUAAGUGCUUUUUUUUCAUCACUUGAUUAUUUUCUUUAAAAUCAGCUAUUACAGGAUAUUUUUUUAUUUUAUACAUGCUGUUUUUUAAUUAAAAUAUAAUCACUGAAGUUUACUAAUUUGAUUUUAUAAGGUUUGUAGCAUUACAGAAUAACUAAACUGGGAUUUAUAAACCAGCUGUGAUUAACAAUGUAAAGUAUUAAUUAUUGAACUUUGAACCAGAUUUUUAGGAAAAUUAUGUUCUUUUUCCCCCUUUAUGGUCUUAACUAAUUUGAAUCCUUCAAGAAGGAUUUUUCCAUACUAUUUUUUAAGAUAGAAGAUAAUUUGUGGGCAGGGGUGGAGGAUGCAUGUAUGAUACUCCAUAAAUUCAACAUUCUUUACUAUAGGUAAUGAAUGAUUAUAAACAAGAUGCAUCUUAGAUAGUAUUAAUAUACUGAGCCUUGGAUUAUAUAUUUAAUAUAGGACCUAUUUUGAAUAUUCAGUUAAUCAUAUGGUUCCUAGCUUACAAGGGCUAGAUCUAAGAUUAUUCCCAUGAGAAAUGUUGAAUUUAUGAAGAAUAGAUUUUAAGGCUUUGAAAAUGGUUAAUUUCUCAAAAACAUCAAUGUCCAAACAUCUACCUUUUUUCAUAGGAGUAGACACUAGCAAGCUGGACAAACUAUCACAAAAGUAUUUGUCACACAUAACCUGUGGUCUGUUGCUGAUUAAUACAGUACUUUUUCUUGUGUGAUUCUUAACAUUAUAGCACAAGUAUUAUCUCAGUGGAUUAUCCGGAAUAACAUCUGAAAGAUGGGUUCAUCUAUGUUUGUGUUUGCUCUUUAAACUAUUGUUUCUCCUAUCCCAAGUUCGCUUUGCAUCUAUCAGUAAAUAAAAUUCUUCAGCUGCCUUAUUAGGAGUGCUAUGAGGGUAACACCUGUUCUGCUUUUCAUCUUGUAUUUAGUUGACUGUAUUAUUUGAUUUCGGAUUGAAUGAAUGUAAAUAGAAAUUAAAUGCAAAUUUGAAUGAACAUAAAUAGAAGUGAUUUAUUUUUUUAUUAUCUUAAAGAUAGGAAGGAAUUAGUAUACGUAUCAGGUGUAUAAAUGGUUUAAAUUUAUUUUAACAUGUCAGAUGUGUUCAAGUUGUCAUAUAAAUAAACUAUGUAUGUAAGGAAUGGGUUAAAA